AGGGCAGGAUGAACGCUGCUUUCCAAGAUGGCGACGGAGGGAGGAGGGAAGGAGAUGAACGAGAUUAAGACCCAAUUCACCACCCGGGAAGGUCUGUACAAGCUGCUGCCGCACUCGGAGUACAGCCGGCCCAACCGGGUGCCCUUCAACUCGCAGGGAUCCAACCCUGUCCGCGUCUCCUUCGUAAACCUCAACGACCAGUCUGGCAACGGCGACCGCCUCUGCUUCAAUGUGGGCCGGGAGCUGUACUUCUAUAUCUACAAGGGGGUCCGCAAGGUACCGACCCGGGCGUCACCGGAGCCAGCCAGCGGCGCUGCUGACUUGAGUAAACCAAUAGAUAAAAGGAUAUACAAAGGAACACAGCCUACUUGUCAUGACUUCAACCACCUAACAGCCACAGCAGAAAGUGUCUCUCUCCUAGUGGGCUUUUCCGCAGGCCAAGUCCAGCUUAUAGACCCAAUCAAAAAAGAAACUAGCAAACUUUUUAAUGAGGAAAACUCUUGUCAGCACUUGUGGAAGGUGGAUUGGAAUGAAGAAAGACAGAAUGAAGGUAGCAAGACCAGUGAGGAGGCUCUAGUAACUGUCCAGGCUGUGAGGCUGAGGCAGACACACUGGGUAGGUCCCACGUCUCCUUGUGGCAUUUAGAUCCAGUCUUACUGAAGGGCAUGCUGAAGAGGAGAUGGCCCUGACUCCUGGGGUAUGGAGGGACACUGCUGCCAGCCCAGGCUGCGUGGCACAUCCUGCCAGCUGCAGGUGCCUCCCAGGCAUGGGGUAAAGCUUAGCAGUGUUCUGUCUAUUCUGAUACAAAGGAAUGGUCUGCACAUUUUGUUAGUUUUGUUUCUGUUGAUUUUCUAAUCGAAGGAAGGAAAUGAGCCCGUAAUGAUCUACUCCUUAAAGCUUGAACACAGAUAAAACGACAUCCGAUCCCAUCUUAAUGUGGCUUUGAAAUACCCUUUCCUAAUACUUCCUGAGCCCUCUUCAGAUGCCUUUACAUCAUCAGAGCCUUUAGUUGCCAUUUUUGCUUGUGGUUGCAUUAUGGCUUUUCAAGCAGCUGCUGUGGUUUUUGAAUUGUUUCAGUAUUUUUGUUAUAAAUUAAUAUCUGCAUUUUGAAAUGCAGAUCCACUCACCCCCAAACUAAUUUUUGAUUUUUGCUUAUCAUAUUGAUAGUAAUGAAAAAAAAGAAAAAGAAAAUGAAGUGCCUUAGAAAGCGUCAGUGUGAAUUGCUUUCACAAAAUGACACUUUGAUGUGGUUAUAGACUUAUUUUUAUUCUUGUUUCAUUUUAACUAGUGUAUUUUGAAAAUCUUGUCUGUUGAUGGCAUUUGGGAUGGUAGUGUUUUCGCUGUUCGUGGGAUUUUUCUUUGUAUUCAUAUCUUAAGUGGCACGGUCUGUUUGGCCUGCAGAGCUGGAACUAUGGGGAGGGCCGCGCUGAGCGUUGAGUGGAGACAUGGAGCCUGCAUCCCCACAGAGCACUGGCCCAGAGCAGGUGUCUUGACGUACAUAGAAAUGUGUCUGUAUUUCGUUUUGCUUUUAAGGUUUAUUUGCGUUUUGGGUUUUUUGUGUUUUUAUGAACGUGUUUGUUAAGAAUGGGCCUUGGAGCAUUUUGGAGUUGGACACUGAUGGAGAGCCCUGUGGCCAGGCCAGCUGCUCUGCCAGCACCUCUGUUACUUCCCCUGCCUUCCCUCCGCCUCCUCGCUGAGCACCUGCCCUGCCCAUCUCUCAGUGUACCCCUGCCCUGGAGGGGCUGCGACUGGGACUGGGGCUCUCCUCCACUGCUUCCCACCAGAGCCUUCCUGCCUCUGCCUGUCUCUGUUCCCCAGCACCUCCCUUCUGGCCCAGGGAGCAGGUCUCUUCCCUGUCCCUCUCUCCUGGAGCUCACCUUCCUCCACCAGGCACCUGCCCUGCACCCUCCUCCCCUACGGUGUCCCUUUGCUCUCAGCACCUUCUCUGCCCCCACCCUGCUUCCCUGUGCUCUCUCCUAAGGACCACCCCCUCCCUGUGCACUCCAUCCCUCUAGGGCUCAGCUUCCUCAAGUCUCAGAGGCCUGUCCUCUGAGGCUCUGGCCUCCUGUGGCAGCUCCUUCCUCUUCUGCCUGCUCUCCUCAUGGCACUUCUGGGUUGUUUGCUUGGAUAUUCCUUCUGCUUUCCUUGUUUUUGUCCUGUGCCCUGUAUGGAGGUUUUUUUUUUUUUUUUUUUUUUUUUGAGACGGAGUCUCGCUCUGUCGCCCAGGCUGGAGUGCAGUGGUGCGAUCUCGGCUCACUGCAAACCUCUGCCUCCCGAGUUCACACCAUUCUCCUGCCUCACCACCUGAGUAGCUGGGACUACAGGCACCCGCCACCAUGCCCAGCUAAUUUUUUUGUAUUUUUAGUAGAGACAGGGUUUCACCAUAUUGGCCAGGAUGGUCUCGAUCUCCUGACCUCGUGAUCCGCCCGCCUUGGCCUCCCAAAGUACUGGGAUUACAGGUGUGAGCCACUGCGCCGGGCCUGUACGGAGGUUUUUUUCAGAGUUUCACACACUCUUCCUCCGCUGCACCUGCUUCCUUGGAGAUAUUUAUUUAUUUAUUUCAGAGACAGGGUCUCACUGUGUCACCCAGGCUGGAGUACAGUGGUGUAAUCAUAACUCACUGCAGCCUUGACCUGGGCUCAAGUGAUCCUCCUUGGAGAUCUUAGGAUGUUACUAUUCGCAGCCAAUUUCUGUGACAUUCGUGGUUAUAUUUAUUAGCUGCAGACCUUUCUAGCUGCAUACUGGGCAAAACCCAGGGGUCUUUACACACCCCCGCUUUCCAUCUUGCCCUCCACCCAGCCACAUUCUGCCACGCUGCCCAUGGUCAAGUUUAAGACCUAUUUGUCCAUGGCAUGGACAGUUGUCAUAGCCUCCUAACUGGUUCCUCAUCACCCCCACCCCACCUUGCAUUCUGCACCUACUGCUGGGGGAUUUCAUGUUAUUCUGCCACUUCCCUUUCUAGAAACUGUCUGUGCCUCCACUGUCUGCAGCAGCAUCCCCAGUAGAAAUACAGUGCCAGCCACGUGUGCAAGUUUAAAUUUUCUAAUUACCACAUUAAAAUAGUAAAAACCAGGUGAAAUUAAUUUUAAGAAAAUACUGUAUUUUAUAUAUAUAUCUCCAAAAUAUUAUUUCAGCAUAUAACCAGUGUAAAAACUAUAAAUGAGAUCAUUGACAUUUUUUUUCAUACCACAUUUUUAGAACCCUGUGUGUGUUUACACUGACAGCACAUUCCACUUGAGACCAGUGCUGCGGGACUGGGGAGUGCAAGCGUCAGGGUCCCAGCCGAAGCCCUUUAGCUUGGGACUUCACAGCCACAGCCUGAGUCCCAGCUCACAACUCCAGACCAAAUUCCCCUCCCAGCUCAUGUGCUGCGAUCAAGACAGAUGCCACACAUGGCCUGGAUCCCCACCCCCCUGGCCUGCUGUGUUGGCUGGGCUUUUCCUUGGAGCAUGGCCCCUGGUGCUUCUGCCACUCCUGCCUCCCUGCCCACCCCCGAAACCCCAUCCCUCAGAGGGACCGGGUAUUUUUCAACAUCCUCAUCCAGAUCAAGGCCCCAUUGACAUUGGAGAGAAUUCAAGCCCAACAGGGAAUUCCAUUACUUAUCAUUGAGCACUGACUAAGAUUUUUUUUUUUAACUAGACUUUUUCUGAAACAAAAAUAUACCUUAUAGUGCAGAAACUGGACUGCAUAAUUUUUAUUCUUGUAUUUAUUUAAUUAAAUGUUCUAGGUAUUUCUUUCUUAAUUUGAAAGACAGGAGAAAAAUGUGUUCUGUUCUCUUCCUCUUUUGUCAAACCCAAUCCAAAUAAGCCAGAGUCAUGUAAGUUAAAUGACUGUGCUUCCCACACUGGCCUGGGGUCUGAGACAGGCUGGUGCCCUGUUCCUUAGAACGCUUGGGAGUGGCCCUGCAGGCUGGUCGUCGGAGCCAGGUGAUGUGUGUCUGUGGAACGGGAGACAGCAUGCUCGCUUUGGGGUCUGAUGGGCCCGUCUGUUCCCCUGGCACUGGUUCGGCUGUGUCUCUCCGCCUCGGAGUCCUUGAAGUUGUUCUCUGUGGGGGUACACUUCCCCAAACAUCCUCUUAGCCUGAUAUUUGCUGUCUUUCUGUCCUUCUGUCUUGCUCAGCUGUCCAGCACCAGCAGAGGAAGAGGCCUUUCUUGGCCAUCCUAUUCAACAUUGAAAUCACUAGAGUCCCCUUCUCCCCAGCACGUUCUCUUCUCUCCCUGGUUUAUUUUUCUCCACAGCACUUAUCAUCAUCAGAUCACAUAAAUUUCACUGUCUUCUCAUCCCACUUGAACCUAAAUUUCAUGAGGGAAAGAUGCCUGUUUUAAUUUAUAUUGUAUCAGUGCCUGGCAUAUGGUACGCACUCAAUACUGGAUGGAUGGAUGGGACUUCAGGCAAGUUUCUUGACCUCUCUAAGCUUCUUUUCUCACUGAUAAUAUGGCGACAAUCCCUGCCUUCCUGUAGGGAGACAGGCAUGACUGCAUUUUCCAUUUUCCAUGCGAGGCAAUUUGGUAACAUCUGUAAAAAUCAUAAAUGUAUAUAUCUUUUGGCUCAGUUACUCCACUGGGAGUUUAUCCUGUAGGUACAUUACUCACACAUGUGAAAAGUGCGUGUGUGCAAGGGCAUUCAUUGCUACAUAGAUGUCCAUCAGUGGGGCACUUCCACAAUAAACCACAGUUUAUCCAAACAGUUGAAUACUCUGCAGCUUUAGAAAAGAAUGAGGAUGCUGUCUUUGUGCCCAUACAGACUGAUGUACAAAUACACUUGGAGGCUGGGCAUGGUGGCUCACGCCUUUAAUCCCAGCACUUCGAGAGGCCAAGGCAGGAGGAUUGCUUUGCUCCUGAAGCCAGGAGUUUGAGACCAGCCUGGACAACAUAGCGACACCCUGUAUUUACAAAAAAUAUAAAUUUUUAAUCAGCUGGGUGUGGCGACACUCACCUGAAGCACCAGCUAUACUCAGGAGGCUGAGGUGGGAGGAUUGCUUCGGCCUGGGAGGUCAAGGCUGCAGUGAGCCGUGAUUGCACCACUGCACUCCAACCU